CCUUUGCUCCCCUGGCGACUGCCUGGACAGUCAGCAAGGAAUUGUCUCCCAGUGCAUUUUGCCCUCCUGGCUGCCAACUCUGGCUGCUAAAGCGGCUGCCACCUGCUGCAGUCUACACAGCUUCGGGAAGAGGAAAGGAACCUCAGACCUUCCAGAUCGCUUCCUCUCGCAACAAACUAUUUGUCGCAGAUGGCUCUUUGCUUUCAUUAGGAAUAAAGAUGGCUGCUGAACCAGUAGAAGACAAUUGCAUCAACUUUGUGGCAAUGAAAUUUAUUGACAAUACGCUUUACUUUAUAGCUGAAGAUGAUGAAAACCUGGAAUCAGAUUACUUUGGCAAGCUUGAAUCUAAAUUAUCAGUCAUAAGAAAUUUGAAUGACCAAGUUCUCUUCAUUGACCAAGGAAAUCGGCCUCUAUUUGAAGAUAUGACUGAUUCUGACUGUAGAGAUAAUGCACCCCGGACCAUAUUUAUUAUAAGUAUGUAUAAAGAUAGCCAGCCUAGAGGUAUGGCUGUAACUAUCUCUGUGAAGUGUGAGAAAAUUUCAACUCUCUCCUGUGAGAACAAAAUUAUUUCCUUUAAGGAAAUGAAUCCUCCUGAUAACAUCAAGGAUACAAAAAGUGACAUCAUAUUCUUUCAGAGAAGUGUCCCAGGACAUGAUAAUAAGAUGCAAUUUGAAUCUUCAUCAUACGAAGGAUACUUUCUAGCUUGUGAAAAAGAGAGAGACCUUUUUAAACUCAUUUUGAAAAAAGAGGAUGAAUUGGGGGAUAGAUCUAUAAUGUUCACUGUUCAAAACGAAGACUAGCUAUUAAAAUUUCAUGCCGGGCGCAGUGGCUCACGCCUGUAAUCCCAGCCCUUUGGGAGGCUGAGGCGGGCAGAUCACCAGAGGUCAGGUGUUCAAGACCAGCCUGACCAACAUGGUGAAACCUCAUCUCUACUAAAAAUACAAAAAAUUAGCUGAGUGUAGUGACGCAUGCCCUCAAUCCCAGCUACUCAAGAGGCUGAGGCAGGAGAAUCACUUGCACUCCGGAGGUAGAGGUUGUGGUGAGCCGAGAUUGCACCAUUGCGCUCUAGCCUGGGCAACAACAGCAAAACUCCAUCUCAAAAAAUAAAAUAAAUAAAUAAACAAAUAAAAAAUUCA